AGAGUGCACCGCAGCCGCUGCAUUCAGGAACCGCUUUAGCUUCGCCCCCGGCCGGCCGGGCGGGGAAGACUGGUGUGGUCUGGCCAUGGAUGGGCUCCAGGCCAGUGCAGGGCCGUUGAGGCGCGGGCGGCCGAAGCGCCGGCGCAAGCCCCAGCCACACAGCGGGUCGGUCCUGGCCCUGCCCUUGAGGUCCAGGAAGAUACGAAAGCAGCUGCGAAGUGUUGUAUCCCGCAUGGCAGCGCUGAGGACGCAGACGCUGCCUAGCGAGAACUCGGAGGAAUCGAGGGUGGAGUCGACGGCCGACGACCUGGGGGACGCGCUACCCGGUGGGGCGGCGGUGGCGGCCGUCCCGGACGCAGCCCGGCGAGAGCCAUACGGCCACCUGGGGCCCGCAGAGCUGCUGGAGGCCUCGCCCGCCGCGCGCUCCCUGCAGACCCCGUCGGCGCGCCUGGUGCCCGCUUCCGCGCCGCCCGCGCGCCUGGUGGAGGUGCCCGCCGCGCCGGUCCGGGUGGUGGAGACCUCGGCCCUGCUGUGCACCGCGCAACACUUAGCGGCCGUCCAGUCGUCCGGGGCCCCUGCGACGGCGUCGGGGCCGCAGGUGGAUAACACGGGUGGGGAGCCGGCCUGGGACUCCCCGCUGCGGCGCGUCUUGGCCGAGCUGAACCGCAUCCCCAGCAGCCGGCGGCGAGCGGCCCGCCUCUUUGAGUGGCUCAUCGCGCCCAUGCCGCCAGAUCACUUUUACCGGCGCCUAUGGGAGCGCGAGGCGGUGCUGGUGCGGCGGCAGGACCACACCUACUACCAGGGACUUUUCUCUACCGCUGACCUGGAUUCGAUGCUGCGCAACGAGGAGGUGCAGUUCGGCCAGCAUUUGGACGCCGCUCGCUACAUCAACGGACGACGCGAGACCCUGAACCCACCCGGCCGCGCGCUGCCCGCCGCCGCGUGGUCCCUGUACCAGGCCGGCUGCUCCCUGCGUCUCCUCUGUCCGCAGGCUUUCUCUACUACUGUGUGGCAGUUUUUGGCUGUGCUUCAAGAGCAGUUUGGAAGCAUGGCAGGCUCCAACGUUUACCUCACGCCCCCUAACUCGCAGGGCUUUGCCCCCCACUACGACGACAUCGAGGCCUUCGUGCUGCAGCUGGAAGGUAGGAAACUCUGGCGUGUAUACCGACCCCGAGUCCCAACCGAGGAACUGGCUCUGACAUCCAGCCCCAACUUCAGUCAGGACGACCUCGGUGAGCCGGUGCUGCAGACCGUGCUGGAACCUGGAGAUUUGCUGUAUUUUCCUCGGGGCUUCAUUCACCAAGCUGAAUGCCAGGAUGGAGUCCACUCUCUGCACCUCACCUUGUCCACGUACCAGCGCAAUACCUGGGGUGACUUCUUAGAGGCCAUACUGCCUCUGGCAGUGCAGGCUGCAAUGGAAGAAAAUGUGGAGUUUCGGAGGGGUCUGCCCCGAGACUUCAUGGAUUACAUGGGGGCCCAGCAUUCAGAUUCUAAGGAUCCGCGAAGAACCGCUUUCAUGGAGAAGGUGCGGGUCUUGGUUGCCCGCCUGGGACACUUUGCUCCUGUUGAUGCUGUGGCCGACCAGCGAGCCAAAGACUUCAUUCACGAUUCUCUGCCCCCUGUUUUGACUGAUAGGGAGAGGGCACUAAGUGUUUACGGGCUUCCAAUUCGCUGGGAGGCUGGAGAACCUGUAAACGUGGGGGCCCAGUUGACAACAGAAACAGAAGUCCAUAUGCUUCAGGAUGGGAUAGCUCGGCUGGUGGGUGAGGGGGGCCAUUUGUUUCUCUAUUACACAGUGGAAAACUCCCGUGUGUAUCAUCUGGAAGAACCCAAGUGCUUGGAAAUAUACCCCCAGCAAGCUGAUGCCAUGGAACUGUUGCUUGGUUCUUAUCCAGAGUUUGUGAGAGUGGGGGACCUGCCCUGUGACAGUGUGGAGGACCAGCUGUCCUUGGCAACCACGUUGUAUGAUAAGGGGCUGCUGCUCACUAAGAUGCCUCUAGCCCUAAAUUAGUUUCUUGUUGAUUGCUGGAAACAAGGCAGUAGUGAUUCUCCGCUGCCACUGCUACCUUUUUUUUUUUUUUUUCCUUAAACUCACGUUCUUACCUUGAUAAGCAUCAGUGUGCUCACAUUUACCUUUAUCACUGCUUCAGUGUCACAAACCUCGGAAGGUCUUCUAGGAAGAACCAUCUCAUCUAGGUACAAAAGGAAAAGGAGAAGUUGGAGGUGGAAAAAAAACCCUUGAUCCGUGAUCAUUUCAGAGCACCAACUUCAUCACCUUCAGGCUUCAGUGUACUGGGUAACACUGACCAUGUCGUUCUGCUUGAGACAGAUAUUAGAUUUUUUUUGGAAUUUGGAUCUUUCAUCUGAGUUCUUUUUCAUGGGCGGGUCGGGUUCGAAGAAACUUCCCCAAAUCUGACAAGUGAAUAUUCUCAUGGUUGGUGGAAAAGUGCCUGAUGUACCAGAAAGAGCACUGGACUUGGAACCAGAAGACCUGGGUUUGGGGUGGUAGCUGGUAGGCAGCUGGCUGAGUGACCUGAGGCUGAUGCUACGCUCAGGCACACAGAUUUUAGUGAAGAAUGAUGAACUUGUGAAAGUUCAGCUGUUUCAGGAGCUCCAGGUCACUGGCAGAGAACCUGGGCCCUUUCCUGGCAUUGUGGACAUGUUCGGAACUGGAGGUGGCCUGCUGGAGUAUCGGGCUAGUCUGCUGGCUGGGAAGGGUUUUGCUGUGAUGGCUCUGGCUUACUAUAACUAUGAAGACCUCCCCAAGACCAUGGAGACGCUCCAUCUGGAGUACUUUGAAGAAGCUGUGAACUACUUGCUCAGUCAUCCUGAGGUAAAAGGUCCAGGAGUUGGGCUGCUUGGAAUUUCCAAAGGGGGUGAGCUCUGCCUUUCCAUGGCCUCUUUCCUGAAGGGCAUCACGGCUGCUGUCGUCAUCAACGGCUCUGUGGCCAAUGUUGGGGGAACCUUACGCUACAAGGGCGAGACCCUGCCCCCUGUGGGCGUCAACAGAAAUCGCAUCAAGGUGACCAAAGAUGGCUAUGCAGACAUUGUGGAUGUCCUGAACAGCCCUUUGGAAGGACCUGACCAGAAGAGCUUCAUUCCUGUGGAAAGGGCAGAGAGCACCUUCCUGUUCCUGGUAGGUCAGGAUGACCACAACUGGAAGAGUGAGUUCUAUGCUAAUGAGGCCUGUAAACGCUUGCAGGCCCAUGGGAGGAGAAAGCCCCAGAUCAUCUGUUACCCAGAGACAGGGCACUAUAUUGAGCCUCCUUACUUCCCCCUGUGUCGGGCUUCCCUGCAUGCCUUGGUGGGCAGUCCUAUUAUCUGGGGAGGGGAGCCCAGGGCUCAUGCCAUGGCUCAGGUGGAUGCUUGGAAACAACUCCAGACUUUCUUCCACAAACACUUGGGUGGCCACGAGGGGACAAUCCCAUCAAAAGUGUAAAUUUUAUUUGAUCAUGUGGCCUCUCUGUUGCUAAUCUCUCCUGGAAACAUCUGCCACAUUUAGUGUGUGUAUGUGUAUUCAUUCUUUCUCAUAACUUCUUAAAGUUUCUUCCCCUCAUUAUUAAAAUGAAUUUACCAGUAA